AGAUCUGGGCAGAGGAACCAAAGGGAAAAGCCACCUUCCCAGGCACAGCCAUAACAUCCACCUCACUCAACUGCUUGUCAAGUUCACCACCAACACAGAGGGGGCUCAGAUAAUCAAGAAACAAUGUCGAGUGAUGAUAAAAGUAAAUCAAAUGACCCCAAGACUGAGCCCAAGAACUGCGAUCCCAAGUGUGAACAAAAGUGUGAGUCCAAAUGCCAGCCCAGCUGUUUAAAGAAGCUGCUGCAACGCUGUUUCGAAAAGUGCCCAUGGGAAAAGUGUCCAGCACCACCCAAGUGCCUGCCCUGCCCCUCGCAGUCUCCUUCAUCCUGCCCUCCCCAGCCCUGCACCAAGCCCUGUCCUCCUAAAUGCCCUUCAUCCUGCCCACAUGCUUGCCCACCUCCCUGCCCUCCCCCAGAGUGAGGCACUGUGGGCACUACCCAACCCCACCACCACUGCCACCUCCACCAUGUACAACGCUGUGGGGCUGGAGACUGAAACCAUGAACUGACAAGUAAACGUGUUCCUCUGCUGUGCAA